ACCAGCAUCAUUCCCCAUGCGAGGUGGCAAAUGCAACAUGCUCUCCAGUUUGGGGUGUCUACUUCUCUGUGGAAGUAUUACACUAGCCCUGGGAAAUGCACAGAAAUUGCCAAAAGGUAAAAGGCCAAACCUCAAAGUCCACAUCAAUACCACAAGUGACUCCAUCCUCUUGAAGUUCUUGCGUCCAAGUCCAAAUGUAAAGCUUGAAGGUCUUCUCCUGGGAUAUGGCAGCAAUGUAUCACCAAACCAGUACUUCCCUCUUCCCGCUGAAGGGAAAUUCACAGAAGCUAUAGUUGAUGCAGAGCCGAAAUAUCUGAUAGUUGUGCGACCUGCUCCACCUCCAAGUCAAAAGAAGUCAUGUUCAGGUAAAACUCGUUCUCGCAAACCUCUGCAGCUGGUGGUUGGCACUCUGACACCGAGCUCGGUCUUCCUGUCCUGGGGUUUCCUCAUCAACCCACACCAUGACUGGACAUUGCCAAGUCACUGUCCCAAUGACAGAUUUUAUACAAUUCGCUAUCGAGAAAAGGAUAAAGAAAAGAAGUGGAUUUUUCAAAUCUGUCCAGCCACUGAAACAAUUGUGGAAAACCUAAAGCCCAACACAGUUUAUGAAUUUGGAGUGAAAGACAAUGUGGAAGGUGGAAUUUGGAGUAAGAUUUUCAAUCACAAGACUGUUGUUGGAAGUAAAAAAGUAAAUGGGAAAAUCCAAAGUACCUAUGACCAAGACCACACAGUGCCAGCAUAUGUCCCAAGGAAACUAAUCCCAAUAACAAUCAUCAAGCAAGUGAUUCAGAAUGUUACUCACAAGGAUUCAGCUAAAUCCCCAGAAAAAGCUCCACUGGGAGGAGUGAUACUAGUCCACCUUAUUAUUCCAGGUCUUAAUGAAACUACUGUAAAACUUCCUGCAUCCCUAAUGUUUGAGAUUUCAGAUGCACUCAAGACACAAUUAGCUAAGAAUGAAACCUUGGCAUUACCUGCCGAAUCUAAAACACCAGAGGUUGAAAAAAUCUCAGCACGACCCACAACAGUGACUCCUGAAACAGUUCCAAGAAGCACUAAACCCACUACGUCUAGUGCAUUAGAUGUUUCAGAAACAACACUGGUUCUCAGCAAAAGGACCCCGGAAACAUUGCAAACUAUUCUAAUACCUCAGUUUGAAUUGCCACUGAGCACUCUAGCUCCAAAAAGCCUUCCAGAAUUUCCUGAGGCAAAAACACCCUUCCCUUUUGAGAAACCUAGGGGCACAUUGGCUUCAAGUGAAAAGCCAUGGAUUGUGCCUACAGCUAAAAUAUCUGAAGAUUCCAAAGUUCUGCAGCCUCAAACUGCAACUUAUGAUGUUUUCUCAAGCCCUACAACAUCAGAUGAGCCUGAGAUAUCAGAUUCCUACACAGCAACAAGUGAUCGUAUUCUGGAUUCUAUCCCACCUAAAACUUCUAGAACUCUUGAACAGCCAAGGGCAACACUGGCUCCAAGUGAAACACCAUUUGUUCCUCAAAAACUGGAAAUCUUUACCAGUCCAGAAAUGCAGCCUACGACACCUGCUCCCCAGCAAACUACAUCUAUCCCUUCUACACCUAAACGACGCCCCCGGCCCAAACCGCCAAGAACCAAACCUGAAAGAACCACAAGUGCCGGAACAAUUACACCUAAAAUUUCUAAAAGCCCUGAACCUACAUGGACAACACCGGCUCCCGGUAAAACACAAUUUAUUUCUCUGAAACCUAAAAUCCCUCUCAGCCCAGAAGUGACACACACCAAACCUGCCCCAGAACCUCAGACUCUACUGCCAUCACAGUCAACAAUAGGACCUGAAACACCAGGAACCAAACCUUCAACAACAUUAGCACCACGAAAGACCAAAAGACCAGGUCGUCGCCCCCGCCCCCGUCCCCGCCCUAAAACCACACCUAGUCCAGAAGUGCCCAAGUCCAAACCCGCUCUGGAACCUGCCACGAUACAACCGGAGCCCUUGGUGCCCACAACUGCCUCAAAACCAUCUGAGAGACCUAAAACCACACACAGACCAGAUGCACCUCAAAUUCAGCCUGGUUCAAAACCACCAAAACAAUUACUUCCUAAACCCCAAACCACAGCAGAACCAGACAUGCCACCAACUAAAUCCGUCUCUGAGCCUGUUCCAUUUGAAACUGAAGCUCCCUCAAUGACCAUAGUUCCCACCACAGACAUUGAGCCUGUAACUGUGAGAACUGAGGCUACAGUGACAACAUUAGCUCCAAAAACAUCGCAACGAACAAGAACACGUCGUCCACGUCCCAAACAUAAAACCACGCCACGCCCAGAGACACUGCAGACCAAACUAGACUUUGGACCUAUUACUCCUGGGACAUCUUCAGCUCCAACAACAACAACAAAAAGAACCCGUCGUCCACAUCCCAAACCUAAAACCACGCCCCAUCCAGAAGUACCUCAAACUAAACUGGUUCCUGCCACAAUCCUCGAACCAGUUCUUAGAACUGAGGCUUCAGGGACAACAGCAGCUCCCAAAGUGCCUCAACGAACUCAUCGUCCACAUCCCAAACCUAAAACCACACUGAGUCCCGAAGAGCUUCAGACUGAACUGGUUCCUGCUACAAUCUUUGAACCAGUUUCUCCUAUAAAAGAGGCUCCAGGGACAACAUUCGUUCCUGUUACAGACCUCGAGCCUGUUACUUUUAGAACUGAGAUCCCUGCAACAACCUUAGCUACCAAAACAUCAAAAAGAACCCGCCCUCCACGUCCCAGACCUAAAACUACACCGAGCCCUCAGGCACCUGAGACCAAACCUGUUCCUGCUACAGUCCUAGAACCUGUCACUCUUAGACCUGAGGCCUCAACAACAUUAGCUUCCAAAACAUCACAACGGACACGUCGUCCACGUCUCAGAACAAAAACCACACCACGUCCUGAAGCACCUGAAUCCAAACCAGUUCCUACUGCGGAGCUCAAACCUGUUACACUCAGAACUGAGACUUGGGUGACAACACAAGCUCCUAAAACAUCACAACGAACUCGUCGUCCACGUCCCAAAACUAAAACCACACCAAGUCCUGAGGUUCCUCAAACCAAACUGGUUCCUUCUACAGAUCUUGAACCUGGUACUCUCAGAACUGAAGCUCCAAAAACCAUGGUUGUUACUACAGUCCUUGAACCUGACACUUUUAGAACCAAGUUUCCAGAAACAACGUUAGCUCCUAAAACACAACGGACACGUCGUCCCCGUCCCAGACCCAAAACUACAUCAAGUCCUGAAGUACCUCAGAACAAAUCGGUUUCUGUUACAGGCUUUGAACCUGUUGUUCAUAGUACUGAUGCUCCAGGAACAACAUUUGCUCUGACUGAACUGCAAACUCUUAUUUUGAAACCAGUGACAUCACCAAGCCUAGAAAUGACAGAAAGUCAACCUGUUUCUGAUGUUCUGGAAUCGGUUACACUUAGUACUGAGUCACCAAAGGAGACCAUAGCACCAGCCAAAACAGACUAUGUAUAUCCCACUGCCAAAGCACCACUCUGGCCAGAGGAGCCAAAGACUGAAGUUGUGGAAUCUAUUACAUAUGUAUCUGAACCACCUGAGACCACACUAGAAACGUCGCCUCUGCCUUCUCAAUCUAUAACCCUACCCAGCCCAGAUGAGCCUCAGACUGAACCUGCUCCCAAGCAGACACCACGUGCUCCUCCUAAGCCAAAAACAUCACCACGCCCAAGAAUCCCACAAACACAACCAGUUCCUAAGGUGCCCCAGCGUGUUACUGCAAAACCAAAAACGUCACCAAGUCCAGAAGUGUCAUACACCACACCUGCUCCAAAAGAUGUGCUCCUUCCUCAUAAACCAUACCCUGAGGUCUCUCAGAGCGAACCUGUUCUGCAGCCUGUUACCUUUAGAUUUGAGCCACCAAAGACAACAAUAGCUCCUCUAGAGACACGAGGCAUCCCUUUUAUACCCAUGAUUUCCCCAAGUCCUAGUCAAGAGGAACUACAGACCACUCUGGAAGAAACAGACCAAUCCACCCAAGAACCUUUCACAACUAAGAUUCCACGAACAACUGAACUAGCAAAGACAACUCAGGCGCCACACAGAUUUUAUACUACUGUGAGGCCCAGAACAUCUGACAAGCCACACAUCAGACCUGUUCUGAAUAGGACAACUACAAGACCUACUAGGCCCAAACCCAGUGGGAUGCCCAGUGGGAAUGGAGUGGGAACAGGGGUCAAGCAAGCACCCAGGCCAUCAGGUGCUGAUAGAAAUGUAUCAGUGGACUCUACCCACCCCACUAAAAAGCCAGGGACUCGCCGCCCACCCUUGCCACCCAGACCUACACACCCACGAAGAAAACCUUUACCACCAAAUAAUGUCACUGGAAAGCCAGGAAGUGCAGGAAUCAUUUCAUCAGGCCCAAUAACUACACCACCCCUGAGGUCAACACCCAGGCCUACUGGAACUCCCUUGGAGAGAAUAGAGACAGAUAUAAAGCAACCAACAGUUCCUGCCUCUGGAGAAGAACUGGAAAAUAUAACUGACUUUAGCUCAAGCCCAACAAGAGAAACUGAUCCUCUUGGGAAGCCAAGAUUCAAAGGACCUCAUGUGCGAUACAUCCAAAAGCCUGACAACAGUCCCUGCUCCAUUACUGACUCUGUCAAACGGUUCCCCAAAGAGGAGGCCACAGAGGGGAAUGCCACCAGCCCACCACAGAACCCACCCACCAACCUCACUGUGGUCACCGUGGAAGGGUGCCCCUCAUUUGUCAUCUUGGACUGGGAAAAGCCACUAAAUGACACUGUCACUGAAUAUGAAGUUAUAUCCAGAGAAAAUGGGUCAUUCAGUGGGAAGAACAAGUCCAUUCAAAUGACAAAUCAGACAUUUUCCACAGUAGAAAAUCUGAAACCAAACACGAGUUAUGAAUUCCAGGUGAAACCCAAAAACCCGCUUGGUGAAGGCCCGGUCAGCAACACAGUGGCAUUCAGUACUGAAUCAGCGGACCCAAGAGUGAGUGAGCCAGUUUCUGCAGGAAGAGAUGCCAUCUGGACUGAAAGACCCUUUAAUUCAGACUCUUACUCAGAGUGUAAGGGCAAACAAUAUGUCAAAAGGACAUGGUAUAAAAAAUUUGUAGGAGUGCAGCUGUGCAACUCUCUCAGAUACAAGAUUUACUUGAGCGACUCCCUCACAGGAAAAUUUUAUAACAUAGGUGAUCAGAGGGGCCAUGGAGAAGAUCACUGCCAGUUUGUGGAUUCAUUUUUAGAUGGACGCACUGGGCAGCAACUCACUUCUGACCAGUUACCAAUCAAAGAAGGUUAUUUCAGAGCAGUUCGCCAGGAACCUGUCCAAUUUGGAGAAAUAGGUGGUCACACCCAAAUCAAUUAUGUUCAGUGGUAUGAAUGUGGGACUACAAUUCCUGGAAAAUGGUAGAUGCUGCACAAAGUUACCUUCUGUUUCAUCAUUGCAAACAAAAAUCAUUGAAAAUACUAUGCCGCAUUCAUUUAAAGCUAUUUUGUUUACUAUGUAUAAAAGUCUACAAUCUAAUUAAUAGCAAUACUAGAUGUUUAUUAUUAGAAAAGAUUGCUGAGAGUAUUUAUCAGGUUUUACAAAGUCAUUUUAAGAAAGCAAGAUACUGAUGUUAACAGAAUAACAUUUUUGGGGAAGCUGGCUCCCUAUUCAUGGUAUUUUAAGAGAUCAUUUGUAUAUUAUUUAUCACACUGUUGUAAUGAUGUUUUGAGAUACUUUUAUAACAAAAUUAACAUCAAAAAGGUAUAUACUUUUUAAAAAAAAUUUACUUUUAUUGAUGUGUACUCUUCCUAUUGAUGAGUUAAUUCCAUAAAUCUCUACUUAGUUUAACUUAUUGGAUCAAAUUAUCUUCAGCAUGUAUAUCUGGGGAAAAAAGGUCCGAAUUUUCACAUUUAUAUUUAAACUUCAAUUUUUUAUAUUUAAACUUCAAUUUUUUAGCAACAGCUGAAUAGCUUUGCGGAGGAGUUUAAUAGUUACACAUUCAUGCUAAUAUACAUUUCCUUUAAACAUCCACAAAUUCUUAAAAAGAUUGAAUCAGUAAAUUUCAUUUCAGCUAAAAAUGGAGUCUAAUAUAUUGUUUCAAAAGAUACAUUUUUACCCACCAUAAAUGUUACAAUAUCUGAAUAUGCUUUGUCAAACUAUCCCUUUAUGCAAUCGUCUUCAUAUUGUUUUUAUGAUUCUAAUCAAGCUGUAUGUAGAGACUGAAUGUGAAGUCAAGUCUGAGCACAAAAAGAUAAUGCACGAUGAGAUUGCCUACCAUUUUAUAGGAUAUUUACUAUGUAUUUAUACGUUAAGACCUCUAUGAAUGAAUGUAUCAGAGAAUGUCUUUGUAACUGUUUAAUUCAAUCUGUAAUAAAAAUCUAACUAACUAACUCAUUUAUUUCUAUUAAAAAGGUAUUGUCCUUUAGGCGGGGAAUGGGAAUCCUUGCUGCACUGUUGCAGUCAUUCUGAAAGGACCUUUCCCUGUACUUACCUUUCAACAUGCUUCAAUCUUAUCAACGCUACAUUUUGUAUUUUUCAAACAAGUAUAAAUUCUGCAAUAAAGAGAUGUAGUUUUUUUUUAAGAUUGAGUUUUUGUUUGUUAUUUCUGAAUGGUUCAUCAGUAUGUUAACUAUACCUUUUAUCGAGAAGGAAAAUCACUAAGUUUUAUUCAGGCUCUACCAACCCCCAUUAUAUCUACUGUUUGUUUAUGUCCUAAAUUAACCUUUCAUCCUAUGAAGUAAUAAAGUUCAUUUUAAACCAA